GGCUCACUGGGGAAGACUGCCGGGAUCCAGGUCUCCGGGGUCCGCUUUGGCCAGAGGCGCGGAAGGAAGCAGUGCCCGGCGACACUGCACCCAUCCCGGCUGCUUUUGCUGCGCCCUCUCAGCUUCCCAAGAAAGAAAACACGGUGAAGGAUGAUGCUGAAGUGCCCGUUUGCAUAUAUUGACAGCAAGACCAGUGUCAAGUAUCAUAAAUAAAUUGCCAGAGAGAAAGUAGGAAGUUUCCAUUGAAGUGGGCAGCUGCAAUGAGCUUCGAUCUCAAGAUUUCUAAAAGCAUUGAAGAAUUUACAUCACUUCAACUAUUAUUUUCUGUUGAACAUGAGAACAGGUAACCUUUUAUGUCUAGUUUAUAUCCAGCAGAUGCUUGUGAUUUCUACCUUUCUGGCACAAAAGUCCUCAUGAUUACACGGCUUCCUCCUCUGCCAAUCAAUGCUAAUGGCAAGAGAAAUGAGAAGCAGUCAUUUUAUAAGCAUUAUGUCUGGAAAUGUUCCUUUCGUUGAUAGCAGUUUCUUAACGCCAGUAUGGUUAGAUGCUAUGGCAACUUAAAAUUGUGUUUCCAUAAUAUAGUGGACAUUGAUGUCAAACUGAUCUGCCUGGGUUUGACUUUGGCCGAAUUAUUUGGUCUAUCUUUGCCUUAUUUUUAUGAUCUGUAAAAUGGGGAUAAUAAAACCCAUCUUGUCAGGCCUUUGGUAAGUGUCAAUCAUAUGCCAUGACAUUUGUCAAGAGGCUUAUGCAUAGGGAUUUUAACCUCUAUUACAAUUAACAACAGCAAUGAGAAUUGUUCCAUUGCAUGCCCAGAUGGAUACUAAAUUAGAAAAAGAAAGAUCCAGGUUGAAAUAAUAACAGCUUUUUUUUAAUAUAGAACUUUAAGUCGUCAAAAUGCUUGUUAUUGUAUAUGCAAAUGUAUACACAUGUAACAUUUUUUUUUUGCAAUAAUUCUGAGGUAAUCAGGGCAGGUGUUGCUAAUGUUUUACAUCAUGAGUCUCAAAGGGGCUACAUAUUUACUACAGCCAAGCAGCUAAUAAAUAGUAGAACUGGGACUUGGACCCUAGUUUUCUAACUCCAAGAUUAUGUCAUUUUUUUUUUUUUUCCUCAGUCAAUCAGCCCUGGUCCUGGUUAGUUGCGUUUCCUUCUCCAGACUCCUUGCUUUCACCCCGAAAAUGAGCAAUUUGGAAAAUAUUAUGUCUAAGGUAGAGUGUUUUAUAAAUCUGUGACUGUAGAACAAUGUCUUAGGAGGUAUCUCAUUGGCCUCGGUGAGAAUUACAACCGGGUACUGCACGGAGAGUCAGAUCCAUAAAGAACCCUUUAUGUCCUUAAGGAUGUGAUUCUGCCACAUUACUCUGACCUACAGAUCAUUCCCCAUCUGCCCCAUCCCCUUCAGGACCCAGGUUUGGGGAUGGGAAGAAAAAGUAGAUGACUCGGUUAGGCACAUGGACAUUUAAUAUUUGGGAAAUGAUAAUAGAGCCUUUCUUAAAAAAAAAGCAAGUUCUGUAUCACCGUUAAUCUCCAUAGUUUUCUACAACAAAAUAAAGGAGAAAAUAUUUUGCUUUAGUUUGGAUUCUAGCGUUGAGUACACAUUUUCUGCUUUCUUCUUUUGAGCUCUUAGUGCCCACAGAAGAGGCUUGACUCUCAUUAAAAUGUGAGUUCUUUCUGUUUAUAGAAAUGAUGGAGACUUGAGAAUGGUAAUACACACUAAGUAGCACUUUUCUGGAAGAUUAUACUUCAGUUUCCCAAUUACAGAGUGAGACAGUGGUGGGGGCAGCAGAUUGAAUGAAUAGAGUAGAUCGUAAGAAGUAGGCUGAGCUUCGGAAUCAGGCUGGGUUUGAAUUCUAGAUACUGCAUGCCUAGCCUGUCCAGACUUAGUUUUCUCACCUGUAAAAUGGUAAUAAACAUGCCUGCCUUCCUUUGCUUCCUUCCUUCCUUCCUUCCUUCCUUCCUUCCUUCCUUCCUUCCUUCCUUCCUCCCUCCCUCCCUUCGUUCCUCUUCCUUCCUUCCUAUUAUCUAUGUAUCUUUCUAUGUAUCUAUCUAUGUAUCUAUGUAUCUAUCUAUCUAUCUAUCUAUCUAUCUAUCUAUCUAUCUAUCUCUAUUUAUUAAUAAGGUUCAAGUAAGAAAAAAUAUAUUAAGCCUCUAGCUUUUAAUAGCUGGCACCUAGAAGGCACUCAGUAAAUAUUCAUUCCUUCCUCUUCAUUCAGUGCUGCUGUUUACCCAAAGCCUCUCUCAUUUGAUGAAUCUCAGAUGGAGAGGGGGAGUAUAUCAAGUAGAUGCCCCAGCUGGUCUAAGAAUGUGCCACAAUUUGGCAAACAAUUGGGAUGGCAAAGGAUAGGAAAUGAAUGUAAUAUUUACCUUAAAAUAUCUCAGAAUCUUUCAUGUGUAGGAGGAAUUAGACCAGUGAUAAAUUGCAGUGCAUGGAUCUUUCACAACAGAAUCAUGUGGAUACCUUCUGAAAUGAGCAGAUAUCUAGGAUAUCUGCACUGAAAUCUAAGAAUCACUGGAUUAGAAUUUUCAGUACUCAGAGGCAGGAUAUUGUAGGGGUUUGAAUUUGGAUUCAAAUUCUGCUCCCUCAGUGUAAACCUAAGGAAGUUAUUUAACUUUUCUAUGUUACUCAUUGGGUUGUGGGGAGAAGUAAGUAAUUUGAUACAUAUGAAGUGCCUAAAACACAGUUUUACUUACUGUAUAAGCCAGUCUUUGAAAUACCUUGCAUGACUUUGUUUAACUUACAUUUUAUUUCCUCUCUAACUAAAUGUCCUAGAUAACUACUUGGCUAACUCUUUCAUUUGCUUAAAGUCUUUUUCAAUAUCUCCUCAGGGAAGCCUACUUGGAUUGCUUGAAUUUGCAUGGGUUGGGGUAGGGGAAGCAGGAAUAGGGCUGCUUGCUCUCUGAAAUCCUGAUCUCCCUUACCCUACUCUUAUUUUUCCUUUAUUCUGUGGCAUUUGGUACCUUAUAAGCUUACACAUACUAUUUUAUUAUUUUAUUUAGUCUAUUUUUAAAAUUUAACUUUUAUUUUAAAUUCAGGGGUACAUGUGCAGGUUUGUUACAUAGGUAACCUUGUGUCGUGGGGAUUUGUUAUACAGAUUAUUUCAUUGCCCAGGUAUUAAGCCUAGCACCCAUUAGUAAUUUUUCCUGAUUCUCUCCCUCCUCCCACCUAUCACCCUCCAAUGGGCCCCAGUGUGUGUUGUUUUCCUUUAUGUGUUCAUGUGUUCUCAUUUAGCUCCCAAUUCUAAGUGAGAACAUGCAGGAUUAGGUUUUCUGUUCCUCUCUUAGUUUGCUAAGGAUAAUGGUCCCCAGCUCUAUCCAUGUUUCGGUAAAGGACAUAAUCUCAUUCCUUUUUAUGGCUGCAUAGUAUUCCACGGUGUAUAUGUACCAUAUUUUCUUUAUCCAGUGUACCAAUGACGGGCAUUUAGGUUGAUUUCAUGUCUUUGCUAUUGUGAAUAGUGCUCAGUGAACAUACACAUGCAUAUGUCUUUAUAAUAGAAUAAUUUAUAUUCCUUUGGGUGUAUACCCAGUAAUGAGAUUGCUGGGUUGAGUGGUAUUUCUUUUUGUAGGUCUUUGAGGAAUUGCCACACUGUCUUCCACAAUGGUUGAACUGAUUUGUACUCCCAGCAACAGUGUAUAGUGUUCCUUUUUCUCUGCAACCUUGCCAGCAUCUGUUAUUUUCUGACUUUUUAAUAGUAGCCAUUCUGACUGGUGUGAGAUGGUAUCUCGUUGUAGUUUUGAUUUGAAUUUCUCUAAUGAUUAGUGAUGUUUUAUUCAUAUGCUUGCUGGUUUCAUGUAUGUCUUUGGAAAGGGUCUGUUCAUGUCCUUUGCUCAUUUUUUCUAAAUAGGUUGUUUUUUCUUGUAAAUUUGUUUAGGUUCCUUCUAGAUGCUGGAUAUUAGACCUUUGUCAGAAGCAUAGUUUGCAAAAUUUUUCUCCCAUUCUGUAGGUUUUCUCUUUGCUCUGUUGAUCAUUUCUUUUGUUGUGCACAAGCUCUUUAAUUAGAUCCUAUUUGUCAAUAUUUGCUUUUGUUGCAACUGCUUUUCGUGUCUUCAUUAUGAAAAAUCUUUGCCCAUUCCUAUGUCCAGAAUGGCACUGCCUAGGUUGUCUUCCAGGGUUUUAAGUCUUUAAUCCAUCCUGAGUUAAUUUUUACGUAUGAUGUAAGGAAGGGGUUCAAUUUCAAUCUUCUUCAUAUGGCUAGCCAGUUACCCCAGCAUUAUUUAUUGAAUAGGAAAUCCUUUCCUCAUUUCUUAUUUUUUAUUUCACCUCCAGUAGAUUAUAAAGUCCACAAGGACAGGGACACUUGAUUUGCUUAUUGCUGUAUCCCAAGUGCCUAGAAUAGUUUCUAGCAAAUAGCAAAUGGCCAAUAAGGAGGCAAUGAUACAUAAAUAAGUAUAUGGAUAGAUGUUAGUGUGAUUAUUUGUCCCCAAGAAGUAGAAAGAGAUAGAACCGGAUAAGACAGUAAAUUAUACAUGUAAUAUUCAAAUAAAAUUUGACAUACAUAUAUGCGCAUAUACACACAUAUAUAUACACAUUUACACACAUACAUAUACAUAUGUAUAUAUAAGUGUAUGUGUGUAUUUUUGGAGUGUUGAGUAUAUAUUUAAAUAUUGAAGUAAUAAUUUAUGUCUAUGUACAUAUAUAUAUGUGUGUACAUGUAUAUAUGUGUAUGUAAAAAUAAGUGUCUAUUUAUCUAUAUAUUUAGGAGUUUUUCAAAGCUACCUGAGGAAACAGAGGUGUUGAAGUGUUUACUUGUUAGGUUGCUAUAGUGAUAGGAAGAAAGAUGAAAAUAUGUACAUAUGAGUCAAGAGACAACAGACAAACAGAAGAAAUAGAAGUGAUUUCAGGACAAGAAAUGAAAGGCUAAGAUUAAAACAGCAACCAACAUUGGAGGGACAUAGAAGAGGGACAGUUUUUAAGUAGACUAGUCAGAGAAGUGAUCUCCGAGAAACUGACAUUUGAACUAAGACAAAAGCCUGAGAAGGACCCACGAUAGGCCUGAGGUCGUCACUGAGGUGGUGGGCCAAGUAAGAGACAGUGAAGAGCUGGAAAUAAGGUUCUAAGAUAGGCAAGGCCUAGGUCAGACUGGUCUUGCAGGCUAUGGUGAGGAGUUUGGAUUUUACGCAAAGUGUAGCAGGAAGUCACUGAACAGACAGAAGCAGGAUGAUGAGCAGGUCAAAGGUGUUUAGAGCCUUGAACAGAGAGUGAAGGAAAAUGGAAGAACUUAUUUAUAAGAUGAGAAGACCAACUGCUCUGAUUUCAUCAUGUAGGCUGUUAUGAACAGAUGAGAAAGACAAUUUGGUUUCAUUGAUGUUUCAUUCAUAGGCUCUCGUUCCCAUUAGAACAUUUCAAAAGGGAAAACAAAAACCCAGCUAAAAUAGGGAAAACCUAUAUAUUCUAGAUGUGGCUUUGCUUUUUCUCAAAUGAUACCAUUCUUAUUUCCAAAUGCAUUAAGUAAUGGAUGGAAAUGUAUGCACUAUUGCUCAAUUCAAUUCAGCUGGAAAUUUUACAGUUCUUGUGUAGGUGUUUUAUGUAAUCAAUUCCCCAAAACACUGAACCUAGAGCUAUUUCCUUAGGAAACUUUAGCUACCAGUUUCUGAAAUCUGUCGUAGUGAAGAGUAAGCAUGUGAAAGGCAAAUUAAAUUCCAUACAAGAUCAAUUUCUUCUUUCUGACUCUACAAAUUUAAAUGGUACCUAACUCUUGAAGAAGUAGCUUACAGGUCAUCUCUUCCGUGAUGUGUUUACUGGGCCCGUGCACAUAUAAUCUCAUACAUGCCUCUUCAUAAUAUGAGUUUAAAAUAGCUUGAUAACAUAUGCCAGACUCCAUUUCAAAUUUUCUAUAAAUAAUUUCUUUUUGAAGUCUCGGAAUAACCGUAUGUGGCAGGUGAAGUUAUAAUCACCAUUUUACACAAGACAAAACUGAGACCCGGAAUCACAGAGUUGAUCAGUGGUAGUGUCAAUAUUGGAAAUUGAGCAAGCUUAAUCAUUAUACUAUUCUGCUCUUUGAUUGUAAAAAGUAAACCUGCACAUUUAUUCACCUCUAUUUGUCCCACUUACUUUGUGGUGCCUUAUAUGAAGGAAUAGUUCAAUAAGCGUAUUGAAUCAGUGAAUUAAUCUGUGACCUAUUCUUUCAAGUUGUAUCAUUUCAUUAGCAAAUAGUGAUAAAAACGUGGGUUUUAGACUGAGGCAACCUAGGUAGCAGAAGGUACUCACUACCUCUGUGAUAUGGUAAAAUUACUAACAUCUCUAAACCUCUUUCUUCAUCUAUGUUGUUGGCACAAAUGUAGGGCCAUUGUGAGGAUUACAUGAAGUGUGCAUGUAAAGCACUUAGCACAGUUCCUGGAACAUAAUUAGAGCUGAGUCUAUCUGAACUGUUUUUAUUAUUUUUUGAACUAAAAUAACCUCCUCAAACAUGAUUACAAUUAUGUACCAGGCAGUUUUUUAGUUGUGCUUGUUUUAUUAACUUUCUUUUAAAAAUCAAAGCCAAAGAUUCAAUCAUAUAAUCAGUGAUGUUAAUUUUGUUCCAGGGCUCAUCCUGGCAUCCUGCCCUCAGCAGGGCAUGCAGUGUGGAUUCUGAAAGGCCCUCUUAUAGGAAGGAAGGCCAGUUCUGGAGAACAGCAUGAGAGCAAAAGGUGCUGUGUGACCACGCUUUUUUCCUCCAUACAUCUGACAUAGCUAAAGGCAGCACUUCCAACCUUGCCUGUCUAUCUCCCUAGCCUGGAUCUACCUUGCUGGAAAGUUACUUUGUAUUCCAGCGAUGAUCCCAGAGCAUUUUGGGUGACAAGGAAAAAACAGCAGAAGACUAAAGUUUUGCCCCAGAUAACACUUAAUGAGGUUAAUUUACAGAACUUGCUGGAGGUUUAGGACCUAAUAUUGAUCCUGUGCCUCUUGUGUACCAGGAGCUGUGCUGAAUGUCUUAGUUUCAUUAUCUCAUUCAAUCCUUACUGCAGCCAUGUACAAAUUUUAGUCGUAAACCAAAUUUACAACUAAAAAAUAAAAAUAAAAAGUGACAUGCUUGACAUGCUUGCCUCUACGUGUGUUUUGCAGGGCUGUGGUGAUAAAAUCAAAUAUUUCUUGUGUUUUGCCACAUUUUUCUUUGAAAGCAAAUUUUGCAGCGUUGCAACACCUCUGGAGUCUCCAGGGACCUCCCCUGCAGUGAAGACACAUUUGGCAGAGAAAUGAGGCAAAGGUUGCAUGUGGAAGGCAGGAAGUUUCAUUCCAGUUGACAGUUUACUUUGACCUGGAAGAAGCUGGUACCAAUGAGCUGAGUUCUAUUUUGUGGAUUACAUUUGUUUGCUUCUUUGUAGGGAACCAAUAUGGUGCUUGUUUACAUUUUUUUUUUUUUUUUUUUGCUUUUGGUCUUGUUAUGGGAUGUUUAAAAGGUGUAACUUUUAUCCUUCUACAUUUUCCAAGUAAAGUUCAGAUGUUUCGAUAUUCCUGACACUAUUUGAUAAAUUAUUUUAAGGAAAGGUCUACACACACACACACACACACACACACACACACACACACACACACGAGAAUGGUGCCUGAUUCAUAAUUGGCACUCACUAUAUAUUUGCUGAAUGAAUACAUAAGAAAAUAAAUGCAUUUCCUUUUUCAUCUUUCUCUCUCUGAGAAUGGGAACUGCUGCAGGAUUUUUUUAAAUGGCAAGUUUCAAUAUAUACCUUUCUUCUUAAAUGUUUGCUUUAAGAAUAAUUUCAGAAGGAGAUUAUUCUAAAAUAUGGAGCAUUACUUAAUCUUAGUUAUGCAGCACAGCUAAUUGGAGUGGACUGUAAUUCCUUUGGAAUUUAUUGAGGUGAGAUCAUUUACUUGUAUACUAAAUGGUCCCAGACUGAUAUACUGUUAAAUUUGUGUAGUCUGAUUUUCAUAAAUUUGCUGGCCUUUCUCUCUCUUAUUGUCUGCUAAUUCUCAUUGCUUUUGGCAUGUCUGGCUCUCCAUUCCCCAUACAAUUAACAGUUUCUACUUUACUGCAGACUAGGAAGCUGGGUAAUGAAUUUGUUGGACCGGGCAUAUAAUAAGAAUACAUAGCUUUGAAUGUGGACUAGAGAGACUCUUUUCCAAGGUAAGGAAGUUAAAAGUUAUGGCUGCUAUAGAAACAGUCUUCAUAUAAGGUGAUACCACACAUAGUAACACUGGGUUUCAGUUGCCUGCGUUAAUAAAAAGGGAGGCUUGGUAGGGAUAAUUCAUUUACUCUUUUGGACAAUAAGCAUUUUCUGAGAAACUUCUGUAGGCAAGACACUGGUGAGAUAUAGAGAAUUAAAAAAGCAAAUACACAAACACAACUGAAAGAUAAAACAUACACAGGGGUUUAUAAUACAAUUUAUACAGUAUUUCAAAUAGCAUGAGAAUACAUAAUGUACUUUGAAAAGAUAUAUAAGGUAAUAAAACAUUUUUGUAUUUCAGAGGAAAGACAAUUGUGUAACUCAGGAAGGGCUUUAUAAGGAAGUUGUAUUUAAAGUGAGUCUUGAAGUGAUGGACAGGUUGGACAGAGAGAGAUUGGUAAGGAGAAGUGGUAAAUGAAUUAUGGUCUGACCGGGGUGAGUGAAUGAUAUGGAUUGUGCGAUUUAUCAGAGAGAGCUACAAUUGUGGGAGAGACUGGGCAACUGAAGGCCUAGGGCAGGAUAUUUGGGAGAUGAGAGAACAGUUAAGAAAUCCUGAGAAGGCACUGGUUAGGAAGUCUGUUGAGGGCUGUUGCCUCUGCCUGUGGCAGGCAGACAGUCAGAAAUGAAAUCUGGAUGUGACGUGGAAAAGGACAGAUUGGAGCCCCUGAGUCUCUAGUUUGAUGAUAUAGGUGUUCUGCAGAAGAGAUUGGUGCUCUUAGCCACGGAAUUUCACAUCUGCCUGGCUUCAGACGGAGGAGUUUAAAGGGAAGAUCUGGCAGGAAUUGAAAGAGCAGUGGGCAGCCAGGCGCAGUGGCUCAGCCUGUAAUCCCCGCACUUUGGGAGGGCCGAGGCAGGUGGAUCAUGAAGUCAGGAGUUCGAGACCAGCCUGGUCAAGAGACCAGCCUGGCCAACGUGGUGAAACCCCUUCUCUACUAAAAAUACAAAAAUGGCCGGGCGUGGUGGCUCAUGCCUGUAAUCCCAGCACUUUGGGAGGCCGAGGCGGGCAGAUCACGAGGUCAAGAGAUCAAGACCAUCUGGCCAACAUGGUGAAACCCCAUCUCUACUAAAAAUACAAAAAUUAGCUGGGUGUGGUGACGCACGCCUGUACUCCCAGCUCCUUGGGAGGCUGAGGCAGGAGAAUCACUUGAACCCGGGAGGCGGAGGUUGCAGUGAGCCGAGAUCGCGCCACUGCACUCCAGCCUGGCGACAGAGCUAGACUGUCUCAAAAGAAAAAAAAAAAAAAAAAUUUAGCCGGGCGUGGUGGCAGUCACCUGUAAUCCCAGCUACUCGGGAGGCUGAGGCAGGAGAAUUGCUUGAAUCCGGGAGGCGGAGGUUGCAGUGAGCCGAAGAUCACAGCGCCACUGCACUCCAGAGUGGGCAACAGAGCGAGACUCUGACUCAAAAAAAAAAAAAAAAAGAAAAGAAAAAGAAAGAGCAGUGGGCCUGGCUGCUGCCCCAUCUAGGAGGUGAGCCAGUGAUCAGCAACAACGUAUGUGAGUUGCAGUACUACCUAGAGGCCUAGACAGACCCUCUGAAUAAAGUUCUCUAUGGGCAGCCCUAACUUGGAACCAUAAAGAGUAAGGAAUUCUAGGAAACAUCAUUCCAGUUUAACUAUUUUUGCACAGUUAGGAAACAGAAGUGACUUUUAUCUUAGAGAAAGGGAAGAUAAUGAAAACAUAAAGUGAAGGAGGGAAACAGGAACCUGCCCUGGAGAGAGCCCAGUCUGACCGGGAGAUAAUAUGUGAAUACAUCAUCAUUGAAUGCAAGGAGGCACUAUUUUUUGGGGACCUUAAAUGCUCUGUUAAGAAAUUCAUACUUAAUCCUAUAAGACAUGGAGACACAAUGAAUAUUCUCGAGUAAGGGAGGGGCAUUAUCAGAUCUGUAUUUUAGAUCUGGCUUAGAGAGGGAAUAAGUGGGGCAAUUAAUGAGGAUUCUAUUAUAAUAAUCAAGGUGGAAAAUUUGCAUUCCCAGAACUUUCUUCUGUUCUCACUAAAGGAGGUGACCCAGAGUCAUCAUAAGAUGUUCUGGACCAUUCUGGGAAUUAAAAAUGCUAGUGUACAUUACAAGCCAAAGUGAUUUCACCUAUGGCUGCUAUUGUCAACUCCGAUGCCCUUAUGGUAUGCCUAGAUAACUCUUCUUAAAAACUCCCUGAUAAGUUUGCUUCUAGUAGGUGAAGAACAAGGAGAAGUGUAUACACAAUUAGAACAUCGGCUUAAAUGAAAUUGGCUUAUGCAAUCAUGUCAGUAUCAUUUUGAGAGGAGAGAUCCUAUAAAAACAAAUACUUAUUACGUAGUAAAUUAAGACUUUGGGGCUUUACUGAGUGGUAACAACAGUAUUCUCUUAUGUGUAUCCAAGUGCCCAACAAGUUACAGACCACUUACAUGUUCAUUAUCUCAUUUGAUUUGAUAACAGCUCUGCAAGGUCAGUUUUAUCUGAAUUAUUACAAGUGAAAAAACUGAAGCUCAGAGGUUGUGAUGACCAUCAAGUGGCCACUUAGCCCCGAUGAUUCAAGAGCUCAUUGGUGUUCUAUAUAUUCAAAGGGCACCAUUCUAUUGCUCAACUUUCCAUUUCGCUCUAUGCACCACUGCCUGAUAAUCUUGGGACAUAUCUUUGUUCAUGCUGUGUCCUUGUUCUAAAUCCAUUCAUCGCUGGGCCCUGUUGCUCACACCUGCGAUCUUAGCACUUUGGGGAACUGAGGUGGGAGGGUCCCUUGAGCCUGGAAGUUUGAGGUUACAGUGAGUCUGGACUGUGCCACCGUACUCUAGCCUGAGCAACAGAGCAAGAACCUGUCUGUAACAAUAAUAAUAAUAAUUAAAAAAAAUCCACCCAUAGUUCUUGGACAUUCUCACUUUAAAGAUCUCUUUCCACCCAAAGAACAGGCUUUUUGUAACCCAGGUGUUACAAUUUCAGCUGUUCUGUUUCCUCACUUUCCUGAAGUAUUUUUACUGCCUUUCCUCAAAGCACAGGACACCAAACACAGGGUAAAGAGGAAAGGGUUCUUUACAAAAGCAUACCUGAGUGGAUACCUUAACACCCUCAGGAAAUCUACACAUCUUUGAAUUAGGGCAUUCCAUAAGUCUUCCCUGUCAGCACUUCCCGGCACAUACUCCUGAAUGUUUAAAAACCAACCAUAUCUCUUGGCUUCCUACUUGUCAAGACACAGCUGAACUUACUCACUUGUCUUGACUUAUGUAAAACACACACUUACAGUCAGUGCUGUAUCACCUAAGACUUCAACAGCCAGCAGCAAGUGAAUUAAGAAACCGUAAUAUAUCCUCCAUUCAAUGCACCCUUGCAGGGUUUUGCACCCCUAAAGAGAUCCCUAGGGCACAUGAAAUCGGGUGACUACCCCAGCUUCUUGCUGUGGGGAAUCUAGGGUUUUUGUAGUUAAUGAUAUUGAGACAUGGACUUAGGGGAACAGGAGGAGGCAUAUAGAAAUCAAGCUUUCGCAGCAGCCAUUAAAUGGAAUACGUGUAAUCGUUCUCAAAGAAUACUAGAUUGCUGGGGCCAAAGAGGCUAAACCUCUGGCUUUGCAGAAAGGCCUCAGAGGAAUAUGUUGUGUUUAUAAAGUCAGCCAAACCUACCUGUAACUGGCUUUCUAGUUCUGGCAUAGUGCACUUUCUGGUAUCAUGCUGCUUCUCUUGUCUUGGUUCUCACACAUGAGUUUUGGCCUAAUUGCUCUAGUUUGAGAGAGUCAAAGGCAAGUCUUCUAGUAAUGAGGGGAAAAAAGGAUAAUAGCUAACAAGUUGAAGUGCUUACUGUGUGCCAGGUGCUUUACAAAAUUACCUCAUAUAAUCAUCUUUCUUUUUUUUUUUUUUUUUUUGAGAUGGAGCCUUGCUCUGUCGCCCAGGCUGGAGUGCAGUGGCACCAUCUCGGCUCACUGCAAGCUUCGCCUCCUGGGUUCACGCCAUUCUCCUGCCUCAGCCUCCCGAGUAGCUGGGACUACAGGUGCCCGCCACCACGCCCUGCUAAUUUUUUGUAUUUUUAGUAGAGACGGGGUUUCACCGUGUUAGCCAGGAUGUUCUCGAUCUCCUGACCUCGUGAUCUGCCCGCCUCGGCCUCCCAAAGUGCUGGGAUAAUCAUCUUGUCUAAUUCCAUGUGAGGUGCUUUACUGACCCUGUCCACCAAUAAGGAAAUUGAGAGUCAAUGUGGUUAAGUAGCUUGUACAGCUGUGGAGAAGGACCUGAACCCAGGUCUAUAUGGCUGUAAAGCUCAUGAUGAAACCCCGUGCUUUGCCUCCCUGUGCUGAGGCGUGCCGUGCAUCCCAUGGCCCCUAUCCAGUUUGCUUGCACGUACAGCUGAACAUCUUAUAACAGGCGUUUAGUUAGUACUCUGAUGUGUCUGACAGUUCCCUAGAAGCUCAGCUUGGACUGAGCCAGCCCAUUUGCGUUUCUGGCCUCUUCUUGCUUCCUUUUCUCCUUUUUCAAUUUCCUUUUUCGGCUCAGGCAGCAUGGGAGAUGCCUUAAUCAAUUGAUGAUAGUUCCUUCUGUUUUAAUGACAUUCUCAUUUCCUCAGUAUGUUUUUCUCACUUUGAGGGUUGGAGAGGGGAGUAAGGGAACAAAUACUUUCAAAAACCCCUAGUCUCCUAGUUUUGAAAGUAAGUUCCAUGACGUUAUGGAAAUGCUGCUUUGAAAUACUGGAACUGCUGUAUUGAAUGCCCAUAGGUGUCUGUGAAAGAGGGAACCGUAGGCCCAACAUGGCUCGAAAGACUUCAUCCAGGAUAAGUAGGUUGACAUGACAAGGGAUUUGGGUCCAGCUCAACAUAAAGAGACAUUUAUUACAAUUAGGGCCAUAUGAAAACUACAUUAGUAAUGAGUUCACCAUCACUAGAGAUAUUAAAAGAGGGCCUAGACAUCUAGUUGGCAAGGAUGUCACAGGGAGAUUUGAAUAUUGGAAAAAGGAGUUUGAAUCAAAAUGACAUUUAAAGGCCUUUCCGGCCUUGAGAUUCUGUCUUGAAUUCACUUAGAAACUUUAUAUUGGGAAUAAAGGUUUCCCCUUGUUAUAAUUAACACCAACUAGUGAUGUCUCCUCCUCCCUCCCCCCUGUGCUUCCCCUGUCUGAACAACUACUCGAUUUAAGAAGGGGACUUAGGAUGAGGAAGGAUGUGGUUCCUUCCCACUUGGCAGCACUCCGUGUCAGAAUGGAAGACUUGUGUCUGGGCCUGGCACGGUUCCGUCAGGCCCUCUUACCAGCCCAGUCGUGUCUGUGACCAGAGCACGUGGGAGGUGCACAUCCGUGUAGAAAAACCUCCCACUGGCUGCCAGCUCUGGAUUUUUGAAAUAAUUCCUAAUGAAUGCAGUCUUGCCCAGGCCAAACCUCUUACAGGAAUGAUGACACACCCUGAAACAAGUCCGAGUCAGGCCAGACAAGCAUCCCCUGAAAAAUACUCCCUUUGCGGUUGGCAGCAUAUGAGAAAGUAUCUUUGAGAGCCGUUUCUUCUUGCCGUUUCAAAGGAAAGCUGCUUGCAGGCCAGGAGGUCAGGAGUGAAAAACUCCUUUUUUUUUUUCUUCUAUUUUUUCUUUUCUUUUAAUUGGCUUACUACUCAUCUGAAAGCUCUGCUAGUCAAAUAUGAUAAUCCUUUGAUUUAAUGUCAGGAUUGAGACAGUUCUCUGGUUCUUGAAGGAAAGAGUGUUGCAAUGCUAGGAAGUCUCCAGCAGCUGAUUAACAGCUUUGAUUUGAAAGAAUAAAAAGAAAGAUACAAAAACUGGCAGUGGGUCCUACCGAUCGGUGCUGCAACUAAGAAUGGACAGUAUUUAAAUAAGAUGAUCUUUCCCCUCAGGAUUUACAGAGACUUCCAUAAUCUCCAGCCCACUUCAUUUUUUUUUUUUAAUGUAAUGUUACAGCUCGGUAUGCUUUGCUCAAAUCUAUCAUGUUUGGAUAUUUCAAACUAGGAAGUUUCAUUCCUUGUAGAAAAGCUUCAGAAACUCACCAGAUAUUUUAAGUCAGGUCAGUCCAGCUCUUCCCAGGAAAUAAAGAUGUUAAGAACUUCAUAGCUGUAGGGACUCCUUAGAGAUCCGAUCCAGUGCUGCCUAUAGGACCUUGGGCCGAGAUUUCCCAUGUACACCAUAAAUCUUCACAAAGUCGUGGGAAAAGAACAGCAACUUCAGCUCCUUUUGCAGCCUGAUCAUUGCUUCUGGGCCCGAGUAGCUGUCUUCUUUUGAUAUAGGACCAUUGCCUGUUCAGACAUGACUCUUUUUCCUGGAUACAAAUGGUAUGUUAUUUUUAGGGGGCAGUUAUAUUUCUUAAUAGUUUUCAGAGUUGGUAGACAGGCCUGAACUGGGAAUCAAAAGCCAUCUUCUCACAUUUCCACUAGUGAGUUAUUGACCUCAUGAAAGUCACCUCUCCUCCCUGGGCCUUUACUUCCCAAAUAGUGUUCCAAAUAACAUUAGUGACUUCUGAGGUCCUGUCUAAUUUUCUAGAUGUCAUCCGGAUAAGAAGAUAAAGUGUAAGAGAAUUAAAAAAAAAAAAAAAAAAAAAGAAAACCAGCAAAGUGAAGUGUGGGGCUUAGGAAAAUGAGAGUCCUCUGUUUAAAAUAUGUCUCAGAGAGCCUUGGUAGCAACAAAGGUCCCAAAUAUAGGAAUCUUAGUCUGUACUGUGUAUUGCAGGGUAUAUGGAUUUCCUGUAUUUGCCUAAGUUCUAUUUGCUAAGAGCUGACUAGAAACAUGAAUAGUAGUCCUGAGGAAGCUUAAAGAUGCUAUCACAUUCAGUUUACUCAUUUGACAUAUCAACCCUGCGGCCUUUGUUCUGGAGGUACACUGAAACUUGAACUCAAGUCUCCUGCCUGCUUGUGCAAUGUGCUUUCAAGUACACUGCCUAUUCAGUUUAUUUAGCAGUGAUGAACGCUUACAGAAACCAUCAAGCUAUGUUUUGAAAGUUAGUUGAUUCAAAACAAUAGAGUUUAGUGGUCAGCCAAACAGAAGCAAGGAGAUUUGCUAGUUUUGCAUAUGUGUGUGACUUAGUUUCCCUAUUAUCCACGUGUUAAACAUAAGUUCUUUGUACAGCUCUAUUCCUGGCCAACAAUUAGUGCUAUUUUUUUUCUCUCGGGUUUUAGAAGAUCUACCUCCUCCAAACAACAGCAAUUAACUACGACUUAUAACUCACUCUCAGCUCCCCACCAGGGCCACUUACAUUCACAUUUCUGAUCACAAUAUUUCUUAAGGUAAAUCUUCAGUUCUCUGAGAAUGCUGAACAAUGAGUGUCUUCUAGCUCAAGUUACAGUUUGUAAUGACCAAUUUUGUAAUUGUGGAACAGCCACAAACACGGUGGCAUAAGAUUCAUGUAUCCUGGCUUAAUAGCUCAGAUUAUUUCCAAAAACCCACUGACGUUGGAUCAAUCAUGCUACCUUUGUCCUUUUGUUUUUCUGUCUAUUAAGUGCUGUGUUUGGCCCAGUCUUCCUCAGGUCUCCUAUGGUCAAGGAUCGUGUUUUAACUGUUUUGAUAGGUUGUCUUUCUCAGGUGUAUUCCAUGCUACACUGCUAUCAUAUAGCAAAGAUCCUGAGAAAUUAUACUUUCAUGAACAAUUCAGGGCUGUGAUUUUGAACAUGAAUUAUUUUUCACUGUGCAUAAUGAUGUUCCCAGAACCUAUUGAAAUACGUAAGACUCUAACGUGAAAUGGCCCCAGACCCCCAUAUUACCAGUUUUUGCUUGUUGGGUUUCUUUUCUUGUUGGGUGUUAGUAGCUCAACUUUCACACCUGCCAUCAACAUGCCUCCUUAUAAAAGCCAUUUGUCCUUCAUGCAAGUUUGUGACUUCUUCUCUGCCUAGGCAUAAGGACUCAGAUAACCAAGUUGUUAUCUGAAGAUCUGUACUAUAAAUAAAGUUGAUUCUUUUUUUAAUUUUUUUUUAAGUUGAUGCAUCUUAGUUACCGUUUGCAGCUCUGGUUUGUCUAGCUGUUGGCUACUGGUAUUUACUUGAUAAUUGACACUGUCUAGUAAUUGAGUUACCAGCUGUUGAGGUAUGACUGCAUGCCUCUGAUUCUGUGGGUCUCACUUUUCUCUUCUUUGGAUGUUUUCACUGGCCAAUAGAUUCGUUUUGUAUUUUUACUGUGAUCUUCUGGGUAGAUGCUAGGGACCCUAAUGAUUUUUAAGUAAUCCUGAAGAAAAUUACCGUAAGCCUAAAGGUGGUUGAAAAUGACAGUUUUUUGCAAAUAAUCAAAAUGCCAUCCAUAGGGACAUGGUUAAAUACACUAUCAUAAGCUAGACAAUGUAAUCAUAUUUAGCCAUUAAAAAUGAUGUAUAAUAGAUCAUAAUGCUACAUAAGUGUGAAUUAGGGUGACAACCAUGGUCUAUGCUUUGCCUAAUAAAGUAUAAUUUAAAAAACAAACAGACAAAAAGAAAUGUAAUUACAUAAGCUAAUCUGGAAAAAAUGUGAAAGACACAUUACUAAAUAAAAUAAGCAUCUUUUAUAUACACAUAUGAUUCAAUUUUUGUAAAAAGAAAAACAGUUAUAUGUGAAAAAAUGAAAGAGUCUGAGUCUAGUAGUUAUAUAUGGUUAUAUUAAGAGAGAGACUGGAUGAAUGCCAAAGGGAGAGGAGAAGGGGCCACAGUGUUUACACUUCCUACCUAAUAUAGAUAUUUUUUUUAACUUUUAGACAUUUACUUAUUUAAAAAAUUAACUUGGAACCUCUUACUAAGUGAGACUCGUAGCCUAUCUCAAAGAGCGAUAAUGUGAUAUUUAAAGAUUUUGCUGAUUUGGACAGAAACAGAAACAAGAAGUGAUAGAGAAUUUAUUAGAUGCUUUACUUUAGAUACAUUUUCUCUUCUUUUUUUUUAUUAUUAAUAAUGUUGGCAGGGAGGCAGUGAACUUGCCCAUUAGAGUUUGGCAACCUGCUUGAGUUUCCUAGGCAUCCCAUGAGUCCUCUCUGUUUCUUGCCACACAGCAUUGACUCAGAUCUAUUCCUUUACAUGCAGGCAGCUGUACGAAAACCUAUGCACUCUUAUAGCCUCAUCUGGUUUCCUUUGUCAAGAUAUUACAUUAUGAAACAUUUUGGGAAAUUAGCAGCUUUUGACAGUAAAUACGAAUGAUUUGUGAUUCCACUAAGCCACUGCUUAAUUUUAGGCUGCUGAAUGGUGAACACUUUAAGGAGCGUGGGAACAGGCCAUAUUUUGUUUUGAUCUUACACAGUCUCAUUUGAAGGAAGGUUAUCCAUUUGAAGAUGGGCUAUAAUUUACAGAAAGGCAAUUAUAUUGAAGACUAAUAAUGAGCAUUUAGUAAUACAUAUCAAAAUGUAGAAUAUGAAUAACUUCAGAAUUUCAAGAUCUUUUAUUCUACAUAAUUAAUUUUUACAGCUGAAAUGUGCCUAUCUUUUUGGCGAUCAGAUACCCCCUGCCCUCCAAAAUACAGGGUUAAAUCUACAUAAGACGUAUACGAUUUCUCCAUGGCAUAUCAUUCUAGGCCUGUUUUCUGUAAUUCCUUGCCUACUCACCUGCAGGUUAUAUUCUAGUCUUACUAGAUUUCUUGUUUUCCUCUAAAUAUCUCAUGUACUUUUCUGUUUUGAGAACUUUACUCAGAUUAUUUUUGCUUUUUGGAAUACCUUCUCUUUUCUUCCCUUCUUUUCUCUUUGCUCUCCACUGUCUCUGUGAUUCUUUCUGGUCCCUAAGUACCCACACAGAAGCACACACCUCUGUUCCUCUUCCUGUUUAGAUGCAAGAUCUUCCCCAUGAACCCUCCCUACCACUAUUAGCUAGCAAGAAUCACUGCUCACUUGGCAUCCACAGCCCUUUAUUUACACUUUAUGCCUUACACUGUUGCUUCUCAAUGUAUGGUCUAAGGAGCAGCAGCAAUAGCAGCCUCUGGGGGUUGACUAGAAAUGCAGAAUCUUGAGUCUUGUCCUAGACUUAUGGAAUGUGUGAAUCUCCAUUUUACCCAGUUUUCCAGAUUCUCCUUAUGCAUGCUACCAUUUGAGAAGCACUGUCUUAGAGCAGAUAUCCAACUUUGCCUUCACUUGGUUGCUUUUGUGUGAGUGGGUUCUGAUAGAAUCUGGCUUGUGAUCACAGACUGUAUCUUCAGCAUUCAUCUGCAAGGCAGGAUGGAGUGCUUUGCACACAGCAGGAGCUCUUAACUGUGUGUUGUUGAAUAAAAGCUUGCAUUUUCAAUGAAGAGGGGUGUUUGAGGGAAAAAACAAAUACAGGGUAUUUCCAUGAUUCUUGUCGGCACGAUGUCUUUCAGAUUGUCUGGUUUCCAUCAUUGCUGUGGUUGGGUUUUAUAGACCCUAGUACAAAGGGACUGAUAUGGUUUGGCUGUAUCCCACCUAAAUUUCAUCUUGUAGUUCCCAUAAUCCCUAUGUGUCAUGGGAGGGACCCAGUGGCAGGUAAUUGAAUCAUGGGGACGGUUACCCCCAUGAUGCCUUUCUUGUGAUAGCAAGUGAGUUCUCACGAGAUCUGAUGGCUUUAUAAGGGGCUCUCCCCUGUUUUGCUCAGUACUUAUUCCUACCACCAUGUGAAGAAGGACGUGUUUGCUUUCCCUUCCUCCAUGAUUGUAAGUUUCCUGAAGCCUCCCCAGCCAUGCUGAUUUGUGAGUCAAUUAAACAUCUUUCCUUUAAAAAUUACCCAGUUUUGGAUAUGUCUUUGUUAGCAGUGUAAGAAUAGACUAAUACAGAGACUUACCACCUUAUCAAAUCUCUUUCCUCCUCUCACCUCUUUGAGAAAGAGUUACAGUGGUGUGGAGGAUUACAGCUUUCAGAAAGAAGCUCAGGUGAGUUCAUUGUCCAGGGGAUUGUAUUUAAAGCAUAGGGAAAUACUUUGUAUUAAUAUUUUAUGAAUAGGACUAUAUCUGUGUAUCUGUGAUGAUUGUAUAUUUGUCCAAGAAUUGGAAGCCUGAUCACAAGGUCAGAGUAAGAUCCAGAAUCAGAAUUUGGUGCCUCUGAACUUAGGAAAAUAACAUUGUUUUAGUUUAUUAUAUUUCCUUUUGCAAAAUUUGACAAGGAAAAGCUUCAUAAUUUCAAAAAUGCUUUUCUAUCUUGUGAUACAGAUUGUAACAGACUUAUAUUCAGAUUUGUUCUCCAAGUAUCUCCAUCUUCCCCACUUCCCCUGGUAUUGCUGUUUUUCUUAGUGUCACUUUUGCCUUCUCCUCUCAUCUGUACAUAUUUCUUUUGCGGUUUUCUUAGUUAUUCUACUCGUAUUCCAAUACUUAAAACAUCUGUAUCAUAUAACUCUGGUGAUAUUCCUGAUCCUUCACAAAAUGUUGUGUAUAAUUAAUAAAAUUACAGUGUGUAUAAAUAUGUAAAAAUAAAUAAGGAUAAAUUAAAAAUAAAAAUAAAAUGAAAUAUAUAAUUAUAAAUAAAAUAAAAUGAAGAUAAAAUGUAAAAAAUAACCUAACAGGUGAUUUUUUUGACAUAGAUAAGAACAACCCUAGUAGGGACUUGCCAUUUUUAUUUCUGUUUUUAAAGCAGAUCUUGAAUAUGUAAUGCCCGUUACAUCCAUUUCUUUUAGAUUAUUAAGAUUAAGACAUUGUUUAAAUACUUCUUUCUACUUUUAUUGGCUAUUUUUUUUAAAAAAUAUAUUUUAUGGUUCCGUGCUCUCCCUCUGGCAUUUGAAUGAUACAAAAAUGAAUUAUAGGAACCAAAACAUAAUGCUACUUGUUUCAUCUUAAAACCUUAAGUUGCUUACAAUGAAAUGAAGGAGGUAAGAUGUUACCACAUAAAGAGAAAACACUGUCAUAGAGUUUUUGUUUAGAGAGAUCUAGGACAUCUUGGAUAUGCAAAAAUGACAAGGUUGGUAGAACAUUGAGGGACAGAUUAGAUGAAUUCUCGUUACUUGUUUUUCCCAUUCACAUAUCCCUCUCUCUCUUCUCUCUUCCGUCCUCUCUGCCUUCCUCCCUCCUUCCCAAGGUGUCUUAUUACCUUUCCCUCCCUUUGUCCUUCUGUUUUUUUCUUUGGUGGAUGAAUGUUUGUAAGAUGUCCAUUUUGAAGCUGAAAGCCUCAAAGGCUCAAAGGCAGAUAAUUCUCUUUUUGGAAGUCAUUUUACAAAAUCCUUUUUAUGAACCUGUCUAUAGGGAAAUUUCUUCCUGUCCUGGCUGUGCAAUGAACCAUUUAUUUGUUCUCAUGGAUACCAAUACUUAUUCAUUAUUUUAAACUUUGUAUUUUCUUUUUUUUUUCCUCCUAAGAAGUUCAUUUUGCUCUUUCUUCUGAUUUUCCUACCUGUUUGUAAUAACAGGAAUUAGUCUUUCCAUGUGUCUGUGUUGAUUUUUUUAAUAUUACUUUAGUGAAAAUUAUAGAGGUUACAGGUUUAGGAGCUGUUGGGGAAAUAAAAUUUAAAACCAAAGUCUCCCAACUGAGAAAUUCUCUCUAUAAAAGUAAGAGAGAAAGAAAACAAAUCUAUUUUUUAUUCUUAAACAAGCAUUAAAUCAGAAUGUGAUGUACAUCACAGGUAAUCCACUAAGAGAUGGCAAAGACAGAAAGAACUCUCACUCUUUUAUGAAGCCAAACAGCCCAUUACAUACGUGUUUUCAAGAUAAACAAUAACUUGUCCUCAAGUAAGCUUGACAGCACCAUUUGUCACACAUAGCUCAUCCUAACUUUACCUGGUAAUUGAGGUGACCAUCCAUGUUAGCUGAUUGGUUUUGGCCAGAGGAAAAACAAACUUCACAUAUCUUUAUGACAGGAGGUAGUUUUUUAACUUGGUGCAAGUUGCCUACCAAAGUUAGGGUCCAACUCUCCCAUAGAAACUGGGAGAUAGGGGUGCUAUCUACCAAAGUUAGGGCCCAACUCUCCCAUAGAAACUGGGAGAUAGGGGUGCUAUCUCCUGUGAUGUUCACUUUUCAAAGAGAUGGCCUCCAGGUCUUCCUAGUAAAAGGCAUUUCUAGGUCACAAAGCUGACAAAAGGCCUUGCUUAGCCUUCAAAAGGAUUUAUAUACAUUUCAAAGAGUACAAAAAGUACUCAGUAAUUGCAAGUUGGCCAAAGUAAAUGCUCUGAGAAAAAGAAAGAAGGUGAAGAAUCUUUUCCCUUAUUUUCAACAAGAAUUAUGCUUCUUAGUUUUAAUUUGUACUUAAUCUGACAGAAGAUAGGUCCUAUUUCAUUAUGUUUAACUAAGCAGUUCAGAAUUAAAGUUUUACUUUUUCUGAGUUUGACAUUCAGCUGACUUUUGUCUUUGGCCUUGUGGUAACAAAUUAUACGCCUCCAAGUUGGAAUCUGAUUUGACAAUUCAUUAGCAUUUCUUUAAUUUGUAUUUUUAUUGUAAUAAAAUUGACCAUUUUAACCAUUUUUAAGUCUACUGUUUUGUGGAGUUAAGUACAUUUUCAUUGUGCAACUAUUGCCACCAUUCAUCCCCAGAAUUUUUCACAUUUUGUACUCAAACUGUAGCCUUUAAACAUUAACUUCUGAGUCUGUCCUCCCCUCAGCCCCUGGCAACAACCAUCAUUAUCACUUUAACCAACCUAUUCGAAAUGCCCAUGAAAUUUCAAUAUCCUGUCUCUGGAUGAGAAGUGGAGAAUUGUGUUUGCCCAGGAUUUUAAAGAUAAAGAUGUUUUCUUGGGAAACUGACUGAGAAAAACAACUUUAAAACCUUGAAUGUGGUGCACCCAUUUAUACAAGUGAUGCCACACUAAUUAUAAAUAACUUAAGUCUGUGCAGUUCCCCAGAAAUGUCUCAUUCGUGCCACUUCAUUACUUUCAAACUGAUAAUAAAAUACCCUCCUAGUGAAAUAUUUUUUUGCAUGUAACUCAGGGAUUUUACUAUUGUAGAUUUGGCAUUUUUCACAACCCUUGCUCCAGUGAAUUUUUAUCUUUCUUAAUUGAUCUUUUGGACACAGCAAACGAAAUAUUGAACACUUCAUAUAUUUUGUUUUAUAAACUGUCGUGGAUAUGAAGGAGAAUGAUGUGAAAGAAUCAGGGCAGACAAUCUGUUGCAGUCAGAGAACCUUAAUUAAAAUGAAGCUUUGCUAUUUGAUUGUCGUGAUAGCUUGAGUUAGACACUUCACCUUUCUGCACCUAAUUUCAUCAUCUGUAAGACAGGAAAAUUAUAUUCCUUUUUGAGUAAGUUGUGUGAAUAUGAAGUAAAAUAAGACAUGAAAAGAAGCACUGUGUAUAGUGUCAAAGCAUGAAUUAUUUCAACUGAGUAAUGUACUUAACAUAUGGCAGAAAUUUGGAAAAUACUUGUUGAGUGAAUGAACAGAUGUUAUUCUCAAGGUUAAUUUUUCUAGGGUUCUCUCUUCUACACACAUACUCCUGUCUUUGCUUAAAACCUACCCUCUCUUGGCUUUCCUCUGAUUCCUGAUUGUAUCUUCUUCUCCUUACCCAAAUUAUGCUUCCAGUUUAAAAACUCCAGAUCUCAGAGUUUGGGUAGUGAUUUGAAAGGGCUCAAGGAAUUUCUGUUAUAUUAUUUCAUAGAAAACUCUUCCUUUCUAAAUGGAACUGCUUCCUGAAAGCUUUUGGGGGUUAGAAAUGGCCAUUCGAGUUAUCCACUGUAACAUACACAAAGAUUAAGGGAAUUUUUUUUUUUUUUUUUUUUGGCUAGCAUCAACAGGCUCAGGGGAGUUCACCCUAGCCAAAAAAAAAUGAUGAGCUGCAAUAAUGUUAAAUCAGACAUGUGAAUCCAAAUUAAACAGAAUUCUUGGUGUAAUUCCAGGCUGUUCCCUCGAUGGUCAUUGGGUGGGGGCUCACUAAGCAACUCUGUUGUUCAGUGUCACCAUACACAUGAUAAAUGCAAAUGUAUGUAUUAUAAAGCAGCAUAACCAAGGCUUACACUGACAAAGGCAGAUGACAAUCCAAAGGUAUUCUGUUGAACAUGCCUUGCCUGACAUGUUUUAGUGGAAAAAUCACCCCCACCCAUGAUGAUCUGAGAAAGAAAUGAGUGUUGAGAGACUGAAGGAGCAGAAAACACAUAAAGGAAUUAUAGUAUUUUCCUGGAUUGAGAAACAGCCUGUAGAAUCACUCUGUUUAGAAGAAUGUAAUCAUUCACUCAAUAAUCCAGAGCGUUUUCUAUAUGCCAGGCUUCAAUGCUAGACCCUGGGAGUCAAAAAUGAAUCAGAAGUGGACCCUGUCUGCAAACGUCUUAAGAGAGAAGACAUACACACUUAUUUAAUAGUACAAGAUAAAAAAGCACAUUACUGAGACUAUAUGGGAAGCAUAGCUAACGUUUUAGGAAGAAGGUAGAAAUUACAUCUGGCAGAGGGAAGCAGGGAGGUUUCAUGAAAGAAGUGGUUUCGGAAAUAUGUCCUGAAGGACAGGUGGUAUGUGUACACUUGGAGAGGGUAAUGAAGGGCAUCCCAGGCAGAAGAGAUGAGUAAAGGGGAAGGAAGGCACGGGGUGAUCUGUAGCAAUAUCUCUAUUUGUACCUGUGGUGGGAGUGCUUGAUAUGUGAGAAGUAGUGGUACAGCAAAGGGUUGGAAAGAGAGCUUGCUGCCAGAUCGUGGGAGGAUUCAGAAUGUCAGUGACGGACAUCAGGGAAGUAGCACUAGGAUAUGAUGUGUGAGCAAAUUGCUUUGGGCUUUGUCAUCAGUCGGCCUUUACAGGUGUUCCCAUGGCACCCAACCCUUACCUGAGGCUUUUACAGCCUUCUUGUUUGCAGUGUGGUAAAUAUCUCUUCCUUUGGAUUUAGAGAAGGAGAUUUCAGGCUGUUUUUUAUAUAUUAGAGAAUGGAAAGAACAUUUGCAUGCAAAAACUCUCAGUUUUUAGGUCACCCUAAUACAUACAUGCAUUUUCUUCCCUUUUUCAGAAAGAGCAGAACAAUUGAAAAUAAUAGCCCUUUUAAUUUUUCUAACAUUAAGGUCACACAGGUGAAAGGGUUAUUUGCUGGGUCUCAUAGGUGCUUACUCCUUUUAUCAUUGGAAAAAUAAAGGCUCCCCUCUGUUUUCUGACUUUUUCUGGAUGGUGUCUUAUGUUCUGAUUUGGCAACAGUCUUUAAGAAUCCAGAAUUCUGGAAGUAGUGAAAUUAUAAUCAACUCCAAUUAGCUACACUGGUGGAGCAUAGCAUUAUCAUACUUAAAUCCACCAGCAUGUCUUACAUCUCAUUUUAGCUAGUCAUUAUGCCAUUGUUCCUCCAUCAGCUUGCCACAGGAGUGGUUUAGCAAAUUAGAAAAUUGAUUUGAAUUUCCUACUUUUUUCCCAAUUAAAAGUUCAUGAGCCUUACUCUAAAACUACCUCCAGUAGGAGUAAUACACCCAGUGAGAGAAUUCCUAGGAAUUCCUCAAAGCUUGGUCUACUGUUUGGGGGCCCUUACACAGUCAAACUCCACCUCCACCGUGUUUUUCUGAAAGAACUUCAUUCAGCAUUUCCAAACUGUGGCAAGGAACCUGAUGAUUGCAGAUGUUACUAAACAAGAAUUACUAAAGUCAAUUAGAUUUGAGAAACACUGUAUAUUAUUACUAAGUAAUUGAGUUUCACAACAUGCAUUAGCAUCCUGAAAGGCCCUGAAAGAAGUCCUGUGGGAAAAGAUAACUUUUGAACCUCUUUCACCUAAUAUUAAUAACCUAAUGUUUCUCUAAACUGAGGGUGAAUUACUAAAGCAUAGCCUUUCAAAAUCAUUCUGUAAAAGCCUAAGCUGAACAAUGUGGUUCAAUAUGUGGCCUUCAGAGGGUCUAAGAUAAUUUAAGAAUGAAAUUUAAAAUAUCAGGAGACUCGAAUUAAGUAGGUACAUUUAUUAGGACUCUGCAUUGUAUCCAUCCUCUAUUUACCUACCAGGAUUUACGUGAAUAUUUUUUCAUAGCCUGGAGAUCCUUUCAAACCCUGUCUGUGUUAACAGAGCUGCUACAUCUGAUAUUAUUUUCCGGAAUCUGAAGAAACACCAAAGAGGACUGAAAUAAUAAGACAUUAAUUUCAGCUGUAGAAUGCCGAUGUUGCUGACCCUGCAGGGUUAUUGCAGAGGGAGAUUAAUUAUGCAUAUCUGCCACCCUAGGCUUUGGAGUUGAAGUACCCUGCUGUAAUUCACUGCCGGAUCAUUCAUGUAGCCAGCAUACUGAUAUGAUUAUUAUUCCACCAAGGUUUUUAUCUGCCCCUAGACAAUUACAGAAGCACUUACCAGCAUCUCUCAUUGACUUCUUAUUUAAAAUUCCCAGGGCCACAGCAGGCAUUCGCAUCCUUUUAUCGGAGACAGCUACAGAUCAAUGACAUGAAGCAACAUGGGAUUUUCUGUAGGACAUGACAAAUGCUGAGAUUGUUGCUAAGCAGAAGAUAGACAUUCAGAUUCCAGUAGAAAAUAGUGUUGCAGUGGCUCUCUAACACAAACUUUUAAGGCAAUGACAAGAACAUACAAUGGAAAUAUUAUGAGAUUUGGUGUCAAGGUAUUUGAGUUUGAACACUGGCUUCACUAUUUGGUGUCCAGGAAGCUAUAGUUCUUCUGUAAAAUGGGAUUGAAAUUAAAUGACAAACUCUUGGCAGCUUGAGGAUCUGGAGAUCUCUUUAGGUUGUGAGAUGAAAUGUAUAUAUGUGUGAAAUCCCUGCUAGGGUAUGUAUAUAUGUGUGAAUCCCUACGAGGUUGUGAAGUUUUAAUGUAUACAUGUGUGAAAAAAAACUUUGUGAGUGACAGAGUGUUUUAAAAAUAUUUUUGUGCUAAUGGGAAUGGCUUUCAUUCCCCGCGUAGUCAUAAUGGAACAUCCUUUUCGUGGCCCCACUGCUUGGGUGAUGACCUAUCGAUGCCUGUAGUCACCUCACACAGAAUGUAGUGACUAUGCAUCGGUAUGAUUAGCAGCUGCAUGCAGUGUACAUCCUUGAAAUGAUGCACAGAAUAAAAUUCCUAUUUCCUAUUGCUGUUCUCAGCCCAGGGUUUUAAGGGACUUCGAACCUGCAAGAUAACAUUCAUCUGAUUUGCAUUUUUUUCAGUUAAGUUUUCCUCUCUGUUCUAUAGAUCAGUGGCAAAAAGUAUGGCUUGUUUUGUUUUAAUUUUCCCCUAAGAGGCUUUCUCCCUUAUGCGUGGCUGCAUCACAGAACGCUACCUGUCUUCAGAGACCAGCUGUAGUGCCAGCUCCAAGGAAUCUUUCCACCCUCACUCCUCAGUCUAAACCCCUUUUCUCUCCCCACAACUCCUACUCUCUACCACAUUAAAAUGCAAGUAAUUCCUUCCCCACAGCAUGCUGGCAUGUUGCUUGGACUGAUUUGUAUACUUAAUAAUAGCAUGAGCAAACACAGCUACAUAGCUUUGUAGAGUUAAAGAAAUAAUAAGAGCAGAUACACUUUUAGGUAUUUUAUAUAUGUUAACUCAUAUAAUCCCCUCAGCAAUCCUAGGAAGUAGAAAUUAUUAUUCUCCCCAUUUUGCAGAUGGGAGAAGUAAGUCACCAAGAGAUUAAGUAACUGGCCCAAUAUUUCAUGGGUACCAUGGGGGCAGAGCCAGGAAUUGGUAAUUAAAAUAAUAGGCUUUUAAACUAUGAGGUUACAAUGAGCCCUAUGCAAAUUGGAGAUUUCUAUAGGUUGUGAGUUCCUGGAUGUCUGAGGCAAUGAAAAUCUGUGUCAUCUAUUCACAUUUAGCGUAAGGGCUCCGCAUAGUAGGUAUCCAGUUACACGAAAUAGCUUUGCAUUGAGAAAAUCGCCCCUUGAAAGCUUAGGAUGUGGCCACAAAAUGCCCCCCUUGUCCUCUGUCAAUAUGUUUUUAGUAUACGUUCUGCAUUCCUGCUCAAUAUGCUUGUCAGAGCAUUUUAAAACCUCACAUAAGCACUGCUUGAGCACCUCUCUGUGAGGGAGGCCAGUGUUCUGUUUUUUUGUAAGUAGCUGUGUGGUAAAGAUAAGGCAUACUUGUUGAAAUUAGGGUUACUUGAGUCUUUAGUGGUUUAUGGAUCAGUAGAUAAUAGCACUAUAACAUUCCAGCUCAUUCGCAUUCUGAUGAAAGGGGAAUUGCAUGGUGUUACUUUAUUUUCAAUAAAGUCACCAAAUGUCAAUGCAUAUGAAAAGAACUCUGGCCAUAGUCCUCCGCCCCUUCCCCCCAUCCAGUGUGAUCUGGUGGACUGAGGUCACAGCCCAGACUAUGGGACUGGUGGGUGCGCAUUGCCAUCUGUCAGGAUGAUCCUGGUGCCCAAAAAUUAGUGAAAGAAGCCAUAGAAUUUUCUCAACAGGGACACAGACUCACACAGACCUCCUCAGUGUUAGUUCAUAAGGGGAUUUUCUUUAACACUUUAGAUACAGAAACAUGAUAUUUCUUUAGGGCUUACUUUUUUGGCUUAUAUGAGUUCCCAGGAAAACCUGGAAUAUUAUCUUUGUGUUUCAGGGACAAAAGUGGGGAUUGGAGCAGUGAGGAUGCAUAAUAGGCUGUUUUCUCCUAUAGGCUGAGAAUACCUGAAGGUAAAGGCUGCACUGAAGCCCCUGUGCUUUCUCCCAGGUGGCGAAGUGUUGGCCUGGUGCACUGGCUUUGACCUGAAGCUUGAAAUUGAGUUUGGGACAAUAAUGUGUCUCAUGGGGAAUUGCAUGGACUCCUUAUCAUAAGCCAAAUGCUGAGGUAAAGCUGCGGAAUUGAGUCGUCCUCCAAGAAGGGAGAGAAAAUGAUGUCUUGUGACAUUUCCAGAUAACUGGCAUCGUCAUGUGAUCAUCACCUAAGAACUAGAACAUCAGCAGGCCCUAGAAGCCUCACUCUUGCCCCUCCCUUUAAUAUCUCAAAGGAUGACACUUCUGUGGUGUGUAGUGAGUCUCUACUUUUAUGGAAUCCUGCAAAGUGAUGCCUCAGAACGCUGCGAUGACUGGGGACUAGACACCAUGAGGCAAAUCCAAGUGUUUGAAGAUGAGCCAGCUCGCAUCAAGUGCCCACUCUUUGAACACUUCUUGAAAUUCAACUACAGCACAGCCCAUUCAGCUGGCCUUACUCUGAUCUGGUAUUGGACUAGGCAGGACCGGGACCUUGAGGAGCCAAUUAACUUCCGCCUCCCCGAGAACCGCAUUAGUAAGGAGAAAGAUGUGCUGUGGUUCCGGCCCACUCUCCUCAAUGACACUGGCAACUAUACCUGCAUGUUAAGGAACACUACAUAUUGCAGCAAAGUUGCAUUUCCCUUGGAAGUUGUUCAAAAAGACAGCUGUUUCAAUUCCCCCAUGAAACUCCCAGUGCAUAAACUGUAUAUAGAAUAUGGCAUUCAGAGGAUCACUUGUCCAAAUGUAGAUGGAUAUUUUCCUUCCAGUGUCAAACCGACUAUCACUUGGUAUAUGGGCUGUUAUAAAAUACAGAAUUUUAAUAAUGUAAUACCCGAAGGUAUGAACUUGAGUUUCCUCAUUGCCUUAAUUUCAAAUAAUGGAAAUUACACAUGUGUUGUUACAUAUCCAGAAAAUGGACGUACGUUUCAUCUCACCAGGACUCUGACUGUAAAGGUAGUAGGCUCUCCAAAAAAUGCAGUGCCCCCUGUGAUCCAUUCACCUAAUGAUCAUGUGGUCUAUGAGAAAGAACCAGGAGAGGAGCUACUCAUUCCCUGUACGGUCUAUUUUAGUUUUCUGAUGGAUUCUCGCAAUGAGGUUUGGUGGACCAUUGAUGGAAAAAAACCUGAUGACAUCACUAUUGAUGUCACCAUUAACGAAAGUAUAAGUCAUAGUAGAACAGAAGAUGAAACAAGAACUCAGAUUUUGAGCAUCAAGAAAGUUACCUCUGAGGAUCUCAAGCGCAGCUAUGUCUGUCAUGCUAGAAGUGCCAAAGGCGAAGUUGCCAAAGCAGCCAAGGUGAAGCAGAAAGUGCCAGCUCCAAGAUACACAGUGGAACUGGCUUGUGGUUUUGGAGCCACAGUCCUGCUAGUGGUGAUUCUCAUUGUUGUUUACCAUGUUUACUGGCUAGAGAUGGUCCUAUUUUACCGGGCUCAUUUUGGAACAGAUGAAACCAUUUUAGAUGGAAAAGAGUAUGAUAUUUAUGUAUCCUAUGCAAGGAAUGCGGAAGAAGAAGAAUUUGUAUUACUGACCCUCCGUGGAGUUUUGGAGAAUGAAUUUGGAUACAAGCUGUGCAUCUUUGACCGAGACAGUCUGCCUGGGGGAAUUGUCACAGAUGAGACUUUGAGCUUCAUUCAGAAAAGCAGACGCCUCCUGGUUGUUCUAAGCCCCAACUACGUGCUCCAGGGAACCCAAGCCCUCCUGGAGCUCAAGGCUGGCCUAGAAAAUAUGGCCUCUCGGGGCAACAUCAACGUCAUUUUAGUACAGUACAAAGCUGUGAAGGAAACGAAGGUGAAAGAGCUGAAGAGGGCUAAGACGGUGCUCACGGUCAUUAAAUGGAAAGGGGAAAAAUCCAAGUAUCCACAGGGCAGGUUCUGGAAGCAGCUGCAGGUGGCCAUGCCAGUGAAGAAAAGUCCCAGGCGGUCUAGCAGUGAUGAGCAGGGCCUCUCGUAUUCAUCUUUGAAAAAUGUAUGAAAGGAAUAAUGAAAAGGGUAAAAAGAACAAGGGGUGCUCCAGGAAGAAAGAGUCCCCCCAGUCUUCAUUCGCAGUUUAUGGUUUCAUAGGCAAAAAUAAUGGUCUAAGCCUCCCAAUAGGGAUAAAUUUAGGGUGACUGUGUGGCUGACUAUUCUGCUUCCUCAGGCAACACUAAAGUUUAGAAAGAUAUCAUCAACGUUCUGUCACCAGUCUCUGAUGCCACUAUGUUCUUUGCAGGCAAAGACUUGUUCAAUGCGAAUUUCCCCUUCUACAUUGUCUAUCCCUGUUUUUAUAUGUCUCCAUUCUUUUUAAAAUCUUAACAUAUGGAGCAGCCUUUCCUAUGAAUUUAAAUAUGCCUUUAAAAUAAGUCACUGUUGACAGGGUCAUGAGUUUCCGAGUAUAGUUUUCUUUUUAUCUUAUUUUUACUCGUCCGUUGAAAAGAUAAUCAAGGCCUACAUUUUAGCUGAGGAUAAUGAACUUUUUUCCUCAUUCGGCUGUAUAAUACAUAACCACAGCAAGACUGACAUCCACUUAGGAUGAUACAAAGCAGUGUAACUGAAAAUGUUUCUUUUAAUUGAUUUAAAGGACUUGUCUUCUAUACCACCCUUGUCCUCAUCUCAGGUAAUUUAUGAAAUCUAUGUAAACUUGAAAAAUAUUUCUUAAUUUUUGUUUUUGCUCCAGUCAAUUCCUGAUUAUCCACAGGUCAACCCACAUUUUUUCAUUCCUUCUCCCUAUCUGCUUAUAUCGCAUUGCUCAUUUAGAGUUUGCAGGAGGCUCCAUACUAGGUUCAGUCUGAAAGAAAUCUCCUAAUGGUGCUAUAGAGAGGGAGGUAACAGAAAGACUCUUUUAGGGCAUUUUUCUGACUCAUGAAAAGAGCACAGAAAAGGAUGUUUGGCAAUUUGUCUUUUAAGUCUUAACCUUGCUAAUGUGAAUACUGGGAAAGUGAUUUUUUCUCACUCGUUUUUGUUGCUCCAUUGUAAAGGGCGGAGGUCAGUCUUAGUGGCCUUGAGAGUUGCUUUUGGCAUUAAUAUUCUAAGAGAAUUAACUGUAUUUCCUGUCACCUAUUCACUAGUGCAGGAAAUAUACUUGCUCCAAAUAAGUCAGUAUGAGAAGUCACUGUCAAUGAAAGUUGUUUUGUUUGUUUUCAGUAAUAUUUUGCUGUUUUUAAGACUUGGAAAACUAAGUGCAGAGUUUACAGAGUGGUAAAUAUCUAUGUUACAUGUAGAUUAUACAUAUAUAUACACACGUGUAUAUGAGAUAUAUAUCUUAUAUCUCCACAAACACAAAUUAUAUAUAUACAUAUCCACACACAUACAUUACAUAUAUCUGUGUAUAUAAAUCCACAUGCACAUGAAAUAUAUAUAUAUAUAUAAUUUGUGUGUGUGUAUGUGUAUGUAUAUGACUUUAAAUAGCUAUGGGUACAAUAUUAAAAACCACUGGAACUCUUGUCCAGUUUUUAAAUUAUGUUUUUACUGGAAUGUUUUUGUGUCAGUGUUUUCUGUACAUAUUAUUUGUUAAUUCACAGCUCACAGAGUGAUAGUUGUCAUAGUUCUUGCCUUCCCUAAGUUUAUAUAAAUAACUUAAGUAUUGCUACAGUUUAUCUAGGUUGCAGUGGCAUCUGCUGUGCACAGAGCUUCCAUGGUCACUGCUAAGCAGUAGCCAGCCAUCGGGCAUUAAUUGAUUUCCUACUAUAUUCCCAGCAGACACAUUUAGAAACUAAGCUAUGUUAACCUCAGUGCUCAACUAUUUGAACUGUUGAGUGAUAAAGGAAACAAAUAUAACUGUAAAUGAAUCUUGGUAUCCUGUGAAACAGAAUAAUUCGUAAUUUAAGAAAGCCCUUAUCCCGGUAACAUGAAUGUUGAUGAACAAAUGUAAAAUUAUAUCCUAUAUUUAAGUACCCAUAAUAAAUCAUUUCCCUCUAUAAGUGUUAUUGAUUAUUUUAAAUUGAAAAAAGUUUCACUUGGAUGAAAAAAGUAGAAAAGUAGGUCAUUCUUGGAUCUACUUUUUUUUAGCCUUAUUAAUAUUUUUCCCUAUUAGAAACCACAAUUACUCCCUCUAUUAACCCUUCACUUACUAGACCAGAAAAGAACUUAUUCCAGAUAAGCUUUGAAUAUCAAUUCUUACAUAAACUUUAGGCAAACAGGGAAUAGUCUAGUCACCAAAGGACCAUUCUCUUGCCAAUGCUGCAUUCCUUUUGCACUUUUGGAUUCCAUAUUUAUCCCAAAUGCUGUUGGGCACCCCUAGAAAUACCUUGAUGUUUUUUCUAUUUAUAUGCCUGCCUUUGGUACUUAAUUUUACAAAUGCUGUAAUAUAAAGCAUAUCAAGUUUAUGUGAUACGUAUCAUUGCAAGAGAAUUUGUUUCAAGAUUUUUUUUUAAUGUUCCAGAAGAUGGCCAAUAGAGAACAUUCAAGGGAAAUGGGGAAACAUAAUUUAGAGAACAAGAACAAACCAUGUCUCAAAUUUUUUUAAAAAAAAUUAAUGGUUUUAAAUAUAUGCUAUAGGGACGUUCCAUGCCCAGGUUAACAAAGAACUGUGAUAUAUAGAGUGUCUAAUUACAAAAUCAUAUACGAUUUAUUUAAUUCUCUUCUGUAUUGUAACUUAGAUGAUUCCCAAGGACUCUAAUAAAAAAUCACUUCAUUGUAUUUGGAAACAAAAACAUCAUUCAUUAAUUACUUAUUUUCUUUCCAUAGGUUUUAAUAUUUUGAGAGUGUCUUUUUUAUUUCAUUCAUGAACUUUUGUAUUUUUCAUUUUUCAUUUGAUUUGUAAAUUUACUUAUGUUAAAAAUAAACCAUUUAUUUUCAGCUUUGAA